AAAAUGAAUGUAUGUACAUUUGUUCCUGAGAUACAGGUUGAUGGACGGAUGGCUACAUGGAUGUGAUGGAGAUGGUUUACUAUCGGGACCUUCCGCAUCCUGCUGAUGUUUUGUUGCUUAGGAUAUGAAUGGCUGAGCGGAGGCUGUACAACCUGGCACUCUGCUUGGGUUAUCAAUACUCUGGCUGACCAUCGUCAUCGUGGGACUGACUUUGGUGGAAGUCCUUGGUUACUUAUCAUUACUGUGUUUCUGAGAAGUUAUAAAUUUGCCAUCUCCCUCUGCACAAGUUACCUUUGUGUGUCUUUCCUGAAGACUAUCUUCCCAUCUCAAAAUGGACAUGAUGGAUCCACGGAUGUACAGCAGAGAGCCAGGAGGUCCAACCGCCGUAGACAGGAAGGAAUUAAAAUUGUCCUGGAAGACAUCUUUACUUUAUGGAGACAGGUGGAAACCAAAGUUCGAGCUAAAAUCCGUAAGAUGAAGGUGACAACAAAAGUCAACCGUCAUGACAAAAUCAAUGGAAAGAGGAAGACCGCCAAAGAACAUCUGAGGAAACUAAGCAUGAAAGAACGUGAGCACAGAGAAGAGGAGAGGCAGGUGUCAGAGGCAGAGGAAAAUGGGAAAUUGGAUAUGAAAGAAAUACACACCUACAUGGAAAUGUUUCAACGUGCGCAAGCGUUGCGGCGGCGGGCAGAGGACUACUACAGAUGCAAAAUCACCCCUUCUGCAAGAAAGCCUCUUUGCAACCGGGUCAGAAUGGCGGCAGUGGAGCAUCGUCAUUCUUCAGGAUUGCCCUACUGGCCCUACCUCACAGCUGAAACUUUAAAAAACAGGAUGGGCCACCAGCCACCUCCUCCAACUCAACAACAUUCUAUAAUUGAUAACUCCCUGAGCCUCAAGACACCUUCCGAGUGUGUGCUCUAUCCCCUUCCACCCUCAGCGGAUGAUAAUCUCAAGACACCUCCCGAGUGUCUGCUCACUCCCCUUCCACCCUCAGCUCUACCCUCAGCGGAUGAUAAUCUCAAGACACCUGCCGAGUGCCUGCUCUAUCCCCUUCCACCCUCAGCGGAUGAUAAUCUCAAGACACCUCCCGAGUGUCUGCUCACUCCCCUUCCACCCUCAGCUCCACCCUCAGCGGAUGAUAAUCUCAAGACACCUCCUGAGUGUGUCUGCUCACUCCCCUUCCACCCUCAGCGGAUGAUAAUCUCAAGAAACUAAGGAAGAAUAAAUAAAUAAUAUAAAAAUAAAAUGAAUACUGCAGUCCUUA